CCCUUUUCUUUUCUGCCGGGUAAUGGCUGCUUCCAAGACCCAGGGGGCUGUCGCCCGAAUGCAGGAAGACCGUGAUGGGAGCUGCAGCACAGUCGGGGGUGUAGGUUAUGGGGACAGUAAGGAUUGUAUCCUGGAGCCGCUUUCCCUGCCAGAAAGUCCAGGUGGCACCACCACUUUAGAAGGUUCUCCAUCUGUGCCUUGUAUUUUCUGUGAAGAACAUUUUCCUGUGGCUGAACAAGACAAACUUCUGAAGCACAUGAUUAUUGAGCAUAAGAUUGUCAUAGCUGAUGUCAAGUUGGUUGCUGAUUUCCAAAGGUACAUUUUAUAUUGGAGGAAAAGGUUCACUGAACAGCCCAUCACAGAUUUUUGUAGUGUAAUAAGAAUUAAUUCCACUGCUCCAUUUGAAGAACAAGAGAAUUAUUUUUUGUUAUGUGACGUUUUACCAGAAGAUAGAAUUCUUAGAGAAGAGCUUCAGAAACAGAGACUGAGAGAAAUUCUGGAACAACAGCAGCAAGAACGAAAUGAUACCAAUUUUCAUGGCGUUUGUAUGUUUUGCAAUGAAGAAUUCCUUGGAAACAGAUCUGUUAUUUUGAACCACAUGGCCAGAGAACAUGCUUUCAACAUUGGAUUGCCAGACAACAUUGUAAACUGCAAUGAAUUUUUGUGUACAUUACAGAAAAAGCUUGACAAUUUGCAGUGCUUGUACUGUGAGAAGACCUUCAGGGACAAAAAUACACUUAAAGAUCACAUGAGGAAAAAACAGCAUCGUAAGAUUAAUCCUAAGAACAGAGAAUAUGACAGAUUUUAUGUCAUCAAUUAUUUGGAACUUGGAAAAUCGUGGGAAGAAGUUCAGUUGGAAGAUGAUCGGGAGUUGCUGGACCAUCAGGAAGAUGACUGGUCUGAUUGGGAAGAACACCCUGCCUCUGCAGUCUGCUUAUUUUGUGAAAAGCAAGCAGAAACAAUUGAGAAGUUGUAUGUCCACAUGGAGGAUGCACACGAAUUUGAUCUUCUCAAAAUAAAGUCAGAACUUGGAUUAAAUUUCUAUCAGCAAGUGAAACUGGUCAAUUUUAUUCGGAGGCAAGUUCACCAAUGCAGAUGUUAUGGCUGCCAUGUGAAGUUCAAAUCCAAAGCAGACUUAAGAACUCACAUGGAAGAAACUAAACACACUUCGCUGCUCCCCGAUAGAAAGACGUGGGAUCAACUGGAGUAUUAUUUUCCAACCUAUGAAAAUGACACUCUCCUGUGUACACUAUCUGACAGUGAAAGUGACCUGACAGCUCAGGAACAAAAUGAAAAUGUUCCCAUCAUCAGUGAAGAUACAUCUAAACUGUAUGCUUUGAAACAAAGCAGUAUUUUGAACCAGUUGCUACUAUAAGAGUACUUGAAAACCUAGAAGAAACUACCACAGAAGCAAUUUUUCAUGUUUUUCUCCUAUGAGACAGAUAUGAAAGAACAAUUUAAAUUUGAACAUCAACAAAAGAUUGGUCCUUGGUGAAAUAAACUUUUCAAAAAUGAAUGUUCUUUUCAAAAAAUAAAGUAGAAAAAUGCACUUACUAAGAACAUGAAAAAAAAUGAAGUAGGAAAAUAAGAUGAAGACUUUGUAUUUUGGCUGUAAAGUUUUAUUGUGUGAUCAUCUUAAAUUAUCUCACUUCAUUAAACUCAUAAUUAUAUAUAGAAGUAUAUGUCAAUUACAAAGAAAUGAAAUGUUCAAAUUAUUUAUAAACCUGAUUUUUCAAUCAGUAGUUUCAGUCUCCUCCCCAAGGACCUUCUUCAUCCAACAAGUUGCAAAAUUUGAAUAUCCCUUCUGUACUAUAUUGGGUGAGCUGUAAAUGUAAUGACUAAAAGAAAAGCCACAGAAGAAAGAAGAAAUGGUCAAAGACGUGGAUAAUAUGCAAAUUGGCCAUUAUAUUAGAACAAUCAAGAGCUGACUGUGUUAUUACCACUUUCUGCCUAGGGUGGCCAAAUUCCCUAGAAAUAGACAUCAAGCCAGUUAACUUCACUUUUCCCUGCAAUUUGUAUGUCACUAACAUUUAAAUGCCAUUUUUUAAAAACAUAACCACAAUACCAUUAUGACACCUAAAAAACAUUAACAUUAACUUAAUAUCAUCUGUUUUCAGUUUUUCCCACUUGUCUCAAAAUGUAUGUUUACAAUAUUAUCAGUUUCAUUACUGAUGAAUAUUAUAUGCCUCCUGAUAAGAUGUACUGAGGAGGACAGAAUAUCACUUUUGUAGAUUUAUACCAAAAAUGCAUAAUUUGGAUAUAAUGAAGAAACAGUCAAAUCCAAGUUUGAGGCUGGGCACAGUAGCUCAUAUCUGUAAUCCCAGCACUUUGGGAGGCCAAGGCAGAGGAUCACAUGAGGUCAGGAGUUCAAGAUCAGCCUGGCCAACGUGGCAAAACCCCAUCUCUACGAAAAAUACACAGAUUAGCCAGGCAUGGUGGAAUGCACCUAUAGUCCCAGCUACUUGGGAGGCUGAAGCACAAGAAUCGCUUGAAUCCAGGAGGCAAAAGUUGCAGUGAGCCGAGAUCACACCACUGCAGUUCAGCCUGGGCAACAGACCAAGACUCUGUCUCAAAAAAAGG